CACUGGCCCCCUCACCUUUUCCUUUCCAGCUGUUUGGGGCUCAGCUAAGUGACCACACAGGAGAGCAGUGAGGCCAUUUGAGGCCUGAGCCUGGUCCUCAGGACUCGACUCUCUCUCCCUGCCAUCAAGCAGCCUGCCCCAGCCCUGCCAGCCAUCUCCACACUCCUGACAGAAUGAAUGCCCUCGAUGGUGUUCCUUUCAAGUUGCCCAAGGGCUUUGUGAUAGGCACAGAGCCUCUCCCUGGGCCAGAACUCAGCGUCCCGGCCUGCGGGGAAGUUCUGCUGGGUUCUAUGCACGACUUCAGCCUGGAGAGGACGGCACUCUUCUGGGUGGAGGCCGCCGGCCAGGGACCCAGCCCGUACCAGUGCGGUGACCCGGGGACAGCGUCAGCCCCUCCAGCCUGGCUCUUGCUAGUCAGCCCCGAACAUGGGCUGGCGCCUGCGCCCACCACAAUCAGAGACCCGGAGGCCGGACACCAGGAGAGGCCGGAGGAGGAGGGUGAGGACGAGGCAGAAGCCUCCUCUGGCAGCGAGGAAGAGCCGGCCCCCAGCAGCCUCCAACCGGGCUCCCCGGCGAGCCCCGGCCCCGGCCGUCGCCUGUGCUCGCUGGACGUGCUACGCGGCGUGCGGUUGGAGCUGGCAGGGGCGCGGCGGCGGCUCUCCGAGGGGAAGCUGGUCUCCCGGCCCCGCGCCCUCCUGCAUGGCCUCCGCGGCCACCGCGCGCUGAGCCUGUGCCCGAGCCCUGCGCAGUCCCCCAGGUCUGCAUCACCCCCGGGGCCCGCGCCCCAGCACCCCGCCGCCCCCGCGUCGCCCCCGCGGCCCUCCACGGCAGGCGCCAUCCCCCCGCUGCGGAGCCACAAGCCUACGGUCGCGUCCCUCAGCCCGUACACCUGUCUGCCACCUCUUGGGGGGGCACCCCAACCUCUCAACCCCCACAAGUCACACCCUGAUACUGCGGCUGACCUGCUGUCCGCCCUGAGCCAGGAGGAGCAAGACCUCAUUGGGCCAGUGGUCGCCCUGGGAUAUCCCCUGCGAAGGGCCAUCAUAGCUCUGCAGAAGACAGGGAGGCAGAGCCUGAGCCAGAGUUCACUCUAUUGGAAGUAUGGCGGAGACUCAUGAUGACACUCCAAGGACAGCACUCUGAGCCACGCUACUAUUUGGAAGCAGGUCUUGACCCCUGAUACAAGCCAAGAAUGUAAGAGCACCUGCAGAGGAGUGAGGGCCCCCAAAGUGCCCAAAAAGAGGUGCUAGUGGCAAGAUACCUGGGAGAAGAAGUGGUAUGAGUGUUAUAGGGGUGUUUCUGUCAUCUCUUUCUGUGUAACAAACUACCCCGAAACUUAGUGGCAUGAGACAACCAUUUAUUUGCUUAUGAUUCUCUGGAUUGGCAGUUUUAAGGUGGACUCAGCUAGGGGGUUCUUCUGCUCAUCUCACCUGCAGUCUCAUGUGGCUACAGUUUGGUGACUUACUUGGGGCUGAAUGAUCUAAGAUGGCCUCAUUCACUGUACAGUGGGUGGUGAUACUUGUCAGCUGGGCCACAUAUCUCCAGCAAGCCACCCUACUUGGUUCCAAGAGUAAGGCCUCUUGAGGCCUCUUGAGGCCUUGGCUGAAAUUGUACAUAGUCACUUCCACCUCAUUCUAUUGGUCAAAGCAUGUUGUUGACCCCUCCAGGCUUACACAGGGGAAAAACAGAUUCCACCUCUUGGUGGGAGAGGGUGCAAAAAAUUUUAUGAUCAUUCUCAGUCUACCACAAGAAGGUUCCAGUGAUCAAGAAAGGCUUCAUGGAGAUACCAAGCAUUGAGCAGGACUUCAAGGAUGGAUAAGAUCUGAUGCUGAAGGAAGGAGAAGGGGUGAUAUUCCAGGAGGGAAGGACAGUGUGAAUAAAGGAGUGGAGGUGGGAAGGAAGUGUUUGGGAGGCCCUGAUCUGACCAGUCUUGUUGAGGAGAGGGUGCAUGAGGCAGGCUGGUAGGAGAUGAGAAAAAGAGAAUUGGGGGUAGAUUUAGGGGUCUUGAAGGCUGGCCUGAGAAUUUGAUAAAUGACCCAAUAGGCAAAAGGAGGCACGGAAGGAUUGUAAGUAGGGUCAGGAGGUAACAUUGAAUGCCAUUGCCUACACCCCCAUGUCCCCACCUGAAAGUAACAUCCUUCGUUGCGUGGUUUUCUAAACAUCGGGACUCUUCAUGGUUUGAUGGCUGGCCCCAGGGUAGUUGGCACUUUUCAUUUUUCUCCCGUUCCUGCCCCACCACCAUCAGAAGGCUUGGACACCUCCAUCAUCACUGAUGAGUACUGAAUGUUGGGUCCCUGCGGUCCAGAGCUGCCUGCUUCUGCCAGAGGGAAUGGCAGAAGGGAAGUGACUUUCAAACAGGAGCCGGGGUGGGGCUGGGCAAAUGCACCUGGUCCCCUUGCCCACCCACUCCUGCUUCUACUCUACUCUGGGUUCAUCAGUUCAUGCCCUGUCCUGGAGGAGAAUUUCCAACAUAGUGACCCCCAUGUGGCUAAAAUGGCAGGGAGGGGUGCUAACAUUUAUUGAACAUUUUCUUGCAUGAAUCUCUCUCUCUGAGGGUAUUCAGUUAGGUCUCAAUUCUGCAAGGUUGCUAUUACAUUAUGACCACUUUGCAGAUGAGGAAACUGAGGCCAGGGAAGUUCAUACAGCCAGUCAAUGGCAGCACUGGGGUUGAGGCCAGCUGGUCUGACUCUGCAUCUUGGUCGCACGAUGUCUUUUAUCUCAUUUUCUGUGUGAGAACCUCCCAGGACAGCACCACAGGCUGAUCUGAGAUUUAAGAGCAGAUCUAAAGUCACGCCUACCUUCGGAUGAUACUGAAAAGCCAGAGUCCUGGCCAAAAAGCUGGUCAGGAGGGCUGUGAGGGGCCAGGUGCACAGUGGGGCUCUGACAUGCCUCCCCAGUCCCUUCAGGCCCUGUGGUAAGGCUGAGGUCUCAGGCCAUCACUCUGGGGGUCUGAAGAUGAGUCAGAGCCAGCCUGGGGCCCUGGCCUCCCAGUGGGUGAGCAGGAAGGAUUUCACUGCAUUGGGAACAUUGUGUUUCCAGAUAUAGACUGGCCACCUGCCUGGCCCCCUGGAUCUCUGGGUGGCCUUCCCUGGUGGGCAGUCAGGAGCCAGGCCCCACGGGGUGGGUCUGAGGGGCCUUUGGAUGACUUCAUCUAUCCUCCCCCACCAAGUUAGUAUUUCUGUCUGUUCUGUGAAGUCCUGGUAACUGAACAAGCCCUUUGGGUUCAGAUUCCUUCUCCCACUGAAAGCCGCAUAUUGCAGUAAAUCCUUUUUGGCCAAGAUAAAUGACAGAUGGCCCAGGAGGAAGGGCAUCAGGUGAUAGAGACAGAGCAGCUAGAAGAGUCAGGGAGAGAAGAAGAUACAAAAGAAAUUGUGCAGCACUCCUUUCCUUCCACAAGGCUUGAUGUGCCCACACUGCCUCCCUGCAGGACAGGCAUGGGUGCCAUGUGUGAGGGUCCACAGGCCAGGCCCCCUCUUUUAGCCUCAGUUUCCCAGUUCACAGGGUGGAGGAGGAAUACGUGUUUGGAACCAGUGACUUCCGGGGGCCCCCUCCGGUGGCCUUAAGGUGACAUCCUCACCCACCUGGGGGCCUGAGGCAAGCCUGAUAGCUUCUACAGUCCUGCAGGCCCAAAAGCUAACCAAGCAGCAGAACCUUUGCAAAUGCAGACUCUCAGGGCUUAUCCUGCAGGGCCCCAGUCAGUGGAUCUGGGGUGGACCCAGGGGCCUUUAAUUUUAGAAAAUUUGCAGAUGGGUCUGAUAUUCACUGUGGCAUAGUAUAGAUCAAGGUCAGCUGUCCCCAUUCACUGAUUCUUAGUCUUGGGUGCACAUUAGAAUCACCUGGAGGGCUAUAGGGAAAAAUUCCAAUGCUCAGGCUACACCCCAGACCAAUUAUAUCGUAACCUCUGAAGGUGAGGCCCAGACAGCAGUAAUGUUUAAAGUUCCUCAGGUGGUUGCAAUAAGCACUGAGACUGAGAACCAUUGCUAUGGAUGAGCCAAAAGGUGGAGGCAGCGUCCACCAUCCAUCCUUGCCCGCCCUCCUUCUGAAGGUGAAGCUUUCACCUUUGGAAACCCUGUCAUCCACCAAGACAGCUAAAAGCCCGUCCUCUAGCAGCUGAUCCCUCUGAUGGACAAGGCAUUAAAUGACAGGUUACAUAAUCGGGGACCUAGUCCUGGGACCCCGGACAAGGCACCUGCCUUGCCUGAACCUCAGUUUCCUCAACUGUGGAAGGAGGGCAUGGGUGCCUGGUUUUCAAAACGUGCUCAGAGCAGGUCUAGCUGUACUGGGCAGUACCUCGGCCAGGAGCACUGGACUCCGGGCCCCCAUGCCCCUGGCCCUGGUUCUCCCAGAGCAGCUCUAAUCUUAGCCUGUUAUUGCUGAAGCCUCCUUGUGCUAAGACAAACACUUCAGGAGCCAAAAACAAUUUGACAACUGUUAGUCUAGAUGAUGUGCACUUUCAUCCCAGCUCUGAAGGUCUACGGAAACCCCACUCUCCCUUCUCCACAUAUACUCAUAAUUCCUGUAGUCUGGAGCCUUCAUUUGGCACCUACACCCCAUAAAUCCUGCUUUGAUUUGCCUGGCACUGAUGUGGUCCUGUAUCUGGUUUAUCUCCCCCACUAAGCUGUGAGUUCCUUGAAGGCAGGUCUUCAUUCAUUUUAUAAACACAGCACACAUUUAUUGAGCUCCUUCUGCCACCAUGCUGGAUGAUGGGGACACUGUGGUGAAUGAGACUGACACAGCCCCUCCCUCAUGGAGCAAAAACUUCGUGGAUGAGAAAGAUUGAGUGAAGCAAUUACAAAGUUAUAUGUGCUGUAACAGGGAAGCAUAGGGUGCUAUGGGGGCACAAGGGACGGCACCCAGGAAGAUAGAGGGGGCAGGAAGCUUCCCAGGGACAGGGAAGGAGGCCAGCCUUGGCUGAGGGAGCUGCAUCUGCAGAGACCUGGAGGGUGAGGGAGGGGCCAAGGCCAUAGACAGGGAGCAGGCCUUUGAGCCCUGCCUGGUAAGGAGCCAGCAUUUUAUCCUGGGCCCCUGAUGACGUAACCGUGGGGUGACCUGAACAGUUUUUCCUGCCUGUGGAAUCCUCCUCUUUGCCUACCCCACACCCCUUCUCCAGCACUGGUGCAGGAGUUGCAUAGUAGUGGCUCAGGAGUCCUGGAUGAGAGAGAUGCAUCUGGGGGCACAGUAGGGGUGCACAGGUGUGGACGGAUGAGGAGGCACCUUCACACGAAUGGGUGCUCCCAGACAGGGGUGGGUGGUGCAUGAAUGUUGAAUUGCGUUGGGUGGUAGGUGGGAUGUCUGUGUUUGAAGCCUGUCCUGCUCCCCACCUAGGUUCUAUGAACACCCUAGCCCACCCUGACAGCCCUUUUCCUGGAGUCCAGCCCCCAGCUUGGCAUAGUUGGUGAAGACCCAUUGUCUGCCUAUCGCCAGGCACUCAGAGAAAGCCUCUAUCCCCCUUCUGUGGGUUCACGGGCUCUCUGGGGCCACGCUGCAGGUGGUGGCUUGCCCUGUUGCCUGGCCCUCAGCUCAGGCCCUUGGAGUGCCUCUCUGCCCUGUCUGCUGCCCCGGCUGCUCCUCUUACCCUCCCUCCCUCUCUGCCCGCUUCCGGCCCAGUUUCUCAGCUACCUCAGUGCCUGUGACCGCCUGUUACGUCAGGGAUAUGAGGAAGGCCUGGUGGAUGAGGCCAUGGAGAUGUUCCAGUUCUCCGAGAGCCAGGUCAGCAGGGCUUCCUGCCAGGGCCCCAGGGGAUGGAAGGGAUGGGGGUGUACCCAGGAGCCCGGUGUGCAGGGCCACACCAGUCCUCAGAGCCAGUCUGUGGGUCCAGCCUGUGGGUCUGUCGGGAGAUUGCCUGACUCCUCAGCUCUGAGGAGGAGAUGGCCCAGGGAGCUACAGCAGGGACAAAGGUGAGAGGCACAGAGGGAGAUCAGGAAGAGGUGGGACGGGGACAGGAGGCAGAGAGCAGCAGGGGUUUUGCUUUAUUAGACUUAAUCAACACAGCCUCUGUGACUGAAUGGCCACUCUUUGUCGGACACUCAGAUAGGAGCCAUGGGCAGCACAAAGAUGCAUGACCUUUCUACUUGGGGAGCGUGCCGCCUACCCCAAGUGCAUGCAGCUGUAGGCCCAAUAGUCACAUCUUGUUUUCUGAGACUGAGUCUCACUCUAUUGCCCAGGCUGGAGUGCAAUGGCACGAUCUUGGCUCACUGCAACCUCUGCCCCCGAGGUUCAAGCAAUUCUCCCGCCUCGGUCUCCCAAGUAGCUGGGAUUACAGGCGCCUGCCACCACACCCUGCUAAUUUUUUUUGUAUUUUCAGUAGAGACGGAGUUUCACCAUGUUGACCAGGCUGGUCUCGAAUGCCUGAUCUCAAGUGAUCCGCCCGCCUCGGCCUCCCAAAGUGCUGGGAUUACAGGCGUGAGCCACCGCACCCGGCCCCAGUAGUCACUUCUAAGUGCCCCAUGGCAGAGCAGCUCUUCACAGAGGCUGAAGGGGACGGAGGGUUGGGUGAGGCCUCGAGAAGGAGAGAGUGAGCAGAGGUGGGGAAGUUUCAAGCCCUGGGGUCGGAGGGGAAGGAAAGUGCAGGCUGCGCUGUGAUACCUCCACAGUGUUCAGGGCACGGGCAGGGACCUUGGGCUGUUUGUGCUCCAGGUGCAGGUGUACGGUCUGCCCCCCUCCUGCCCCAGCAGAAAGUUGACAGUGAGUGGGAGGAGUGGGAGGAGAGUCAGGACAGAGCCCAUGGCCAGGCUGGGGCCUUCUUUCCUUGGCAGAGGAAGGGAGGUCGGAACCUACAUCACCCUACAGGUACAGAAAAGUGGCAGGUGUGGCCCAGGAUCAGGCUCACGUGGCCUGGGGGUAGCCACAGCUUUUUGGGACUAGGUGCAGUAGGCACUGGAGCUGGGGCUCCCCAUGGCUGAGGCCAGGCCCAGCAGAGCCCCCAGCACCCUCCCUGUCUCCUCUUCCUCAGGCAGGGGAGUUCCUGCGCCUCUGGGAGCAGUUCAGUGACAUGGGCUUCCAGCAGGACCGGAUCAAGGAGGUGCUGCUGGUCCAUGGCAACCGCCGAGAGCAAGCCCUGGAGGAGCUGGUGGCCUGUGCCCAGUGACCACGGAGGCACUCCACGAUGCCUGGGCAUCUAGGCCCAAUGCCAGACCUGGCAACCCAUCCUAACUGUAUUAUUAAAACCAAGUAAGAGUAACAAAGUGAUGCAUACUUAUUGUAAAAACACAAAUAAUACCAAGGGUGACAGUUAACAGCAGCAGAAUCUGCUGAAAGAGUUGAAAUAGUUGCCUCUGCAGAGGGGCAGAUGGGAGAGCCGGACGGGGAGCUAUGUUCUUCAUGCAUGCCUGUGAAACCACCUGAUUUGACUCUUUACACUGUGUGCAUUAGUAACCUUGAUUUUAAGAAAAUUAAAACAAAUAAAUAAUGGGCAGUUCUUCUGA